ACUUCAUCCAAGCCCAGCUUCGCAGACCUCUGGCGCCCGGCGGGUUCCCAGUUCCCCCGCUUCUUCCGAGGAGACAGCGGAGGCGAGGCCACCGGGCUGUCAGGCUGAAGCUCCGUGGCCGCCGGGUCCUGCACGCAGAGAAGACCCCAGCGCCGGCGCGGCUCAGGGCUGGGCCCACGGGACUCCGGACGCGCCGCGAAAGCGUUGCGCUCCCGGAGGCGUCCGCAGCUGCUGGCUGCUCAUUUGCCGGUGACCGGAGAGCUGCGCGUUUGCCAGAGUUCCAGCGGACCUCCUGGAGCGCUUGAACCCAAAGCCCCGUUUCACAGAUGAGAAUACCGAGUCCCCCUGGAAGAAGUGACUGGCUCGGGGCCAGCAUGGCCCCCACGCUGCAACAGGCGUACCGGAGGCGCUGGUGGAUGGCCUGCACGGCUGUGCUGGAGAACCUCUUCUUCUCUGCUGUACUCCUGGGCUGGGGCUCCCUGUUGAUCAUUCUGAAGAACGAGGGCUUCUAUUCCAGCACGUGCCCAGCUGAGAGCAGCACCAACACCACCCAGGAUGAGCAGCGCAGGUGGCCAGGCUGUGACCAGCAGGACGAGAUGCUCAACCUGGGCUUCACCAUUGGUUCCUUCGUGCUCAGCGCCACCACCCUGCCACUGGGGAUCCUCAUGGACCGCUUUGGCCCCCGACCCGUGCGGCUGGUUGGCAGUGCCUGCUUCACUGCGUCCUGCACCCUCAUGGCCCUGGCCUCCCGGGACGUGGAAGCUCUGUCUCCGUUGAUAUUCCUGGCGCUGUCCCUGAAUGGCUUUGGUGGCAUCUGCCUAACGUUCACUUCACUCACGCUGCCCAACAUGUUUGGGAACCUGCGCUCCACGUUAAUGGCCCUCAUGAUUGGCUCUUACGCCUCUUCUGCCAUUACGUUCCCAGGAAUCAAGCUGAUCUACGAUGCCGGUGUGGCCUUCGUGGUCAUCAUGUUCACCUGGUCUGGCCUGGCCUGCCUUAUCUUUCUGAACUGCACCCUCAACUGGCCCAUCGAAGCCUUUCCUGCCCCUGAGGAAGUCAAUUACACGAAGAAGAUCAAGCUGAGUGGGCUGGCCCUGGACCACAAGGUGACAGGUGACCUCUUCUACACCCAUGUGACCACCAUGGGCCAGAGGCUCAGCCAGAAGGCCCCCAGCCUGGAGGACGGUUCGGAUGCCUUCAUGUCACCCCAGGAUGUUCGGGGCACCUCAGAAAACCUUCCUGAGAGGUCUGUCCCCUUACGCAAGAGCCUCUGCUCCCCCACUUUCCUGUGGAGCCUCCUCACCAUGGGCAUGACCCAGCUGCGGAUCAUCUUCUACAUGGCUGCUGUGAACAAGAUGCUGGAGUACCUUGUGACUGGUGGCCAGGAGCAUGAGACAAAUGAACAGCAACAAAAGGUGGCAGAGACAGUUGGGUUCUACUCCUCCGUCUUCGGGGCCAUGCAGCUGUUGUGCCUUCUCACCUGCCCCCUCAUUGGCUACAUCAUGGACUGGCGGAUCAAGGACUGCGUGGACGCCCCAACUCAGGGCACUGUCCUCGGAGAUGCCAGGGACGGGGUUGCUACCAAAUCCAUCAGACCACGCUACUGCAAGAUCCAAAAGCUCACCAAUGCCAUCAGUGCCUUCACCCUGACCAACCUGCUGCUUGUGGGUUUUGGCAUCACCUGUCUCAUCAACAACUUACACCUCCAGUUUGUGACCUUUGUCCUGCACACCAUUGUUCGAGGUUUCUUCCACUCAGCCUGUGGGAGUCUCUAUGCUGCAGUGUUCCCAUCCAACCACUUUGGGACGCUGACAGGCCUGCAGUCCCUCAUCAGUGCUGUGUUCGCCUUGCUUCAGCAGCCACUUUUCAUGGCGAUGGUGGGACCCCUGAAAGGAGAGCCCUUCUGGGUGAAUCUGGGCCUCCUGCUAUUCUCACUCCUGGGAUUCCUGUUGCCUUCCUACCUCUUCUAUUACCGUGCCCGGCUCCAGCAGGAGUACGCCGCCAAUGGGAUGGGCCCACUGAAGGUGCUUAGCGGCUCUGAGGUGACCGCAUAGACUUCUCAGACCAAGGGACCUGGAUGACAGGCAAUCAAGGCCUGAGCAACCAAAAGGAGUGCCCCAUAUGGCUUUUCUACCUGUAACAUGCACAUAGAGCCAUGGCCGUAGAUUUAUAAAUACCAAGAGAAGUUCUAUUUUUGUAAAGACUGCAAAAAGGAGGAAAAAAAACCUUCAAAAACGCCCCCUAAGUCAACGCUCCAUUGACUGAAGACAGUCCCUAUCCUAGAGGGGUUGAGCCUUCUUCCUCCUUGGGUUGGAGGAGACCAGGGUGCCUCUUAUCUCCUUCUAGCGGUCUGCCUCCUGGUACCUCUUGGGGGGAUCGGCAAACAGGCUACCCCUGAGGUCCCAUGUGCCAUGAGUGUGCACACAUGCAUGUGUCUGUGUAUGUGUGAAUGUGAGAGAGACACAGCCCUCCUUUCAGAAGGAAAGGGGCCUGAGGUGCCAGCUGUGUCCUGGGUUAGGGGUUGGGGGUCGGCCCCUUCCAGGGCCAGGAGGGCAGGUUCCCUCUCUGGUGCUGCUGCUUGCAAGUCUUAGAGGAAAUAAAAAGGGAAGUGAGAGA